AGUGGCAGGAGUGUGGCGGCCCGGCCUCCGCAGGCUACCCGGGGUUGAAGCUACUGCGAGCUCCGGUGGCUGCCUGGGGACGCUCAGGGACGCUCAUUCCUGGCCAGAGUCCUGACUUCUUUCUCGGAUCGAGAUCUCGUUGCUGGCUCGAGGAAAUCACCGGCUCUUCUCCCGGAUCCUUUUCUUCUCUCACUUGCUGGCUUUCUUCUUCCUGCCUCCCUGGCUUCCAUCUCCCAACCCCGCGAUUCCCUCCUCUACUCCCGUGCUCCCGUCGCCCGCCAUCCUGAGCCAUCCCACCUGCAACCUUCUGUCUUUUGCCCCUCCUUGACCUCAGAGGGUCCUGCCUUAAGCUUCUCACCAGAAUCUCCUAGAUUUCUAUCUCUUCCCUGCUUGCCAGCUCUUGACUCCCAAAUUCCAGCUGACGUUUGACCACUUGACAUUUGACCCUGACACCCUUGACUGCAAAUCUAAAUUCUUAUCUUCUGCAACCUGUACUGCUGAAACAGGCCUUCCCCCUGUCUUCCAACCCCGCUUUCUGACACCCAUUUUUACUUUCUUACUCUUGGGUCAGUUCCUGCUACAGCUAUCCCACCAUGGACUUCUUGAUGAGUGGCCUGGCAGCCUGCGGGGCCUGUGUAUUCACCAAUCCCCUGGAGGUGGUGAAGACCAGGAUGCAGUUGCAAGGAGAACUGCAGGCCCCUGGCACAUACCAGCGGCACUACCGAAAUGUCUUCCAUGCCUUCAUCACCAUCGGCAAGGUGGAUGGCCUUGCUGCCCUGCAGAAAGGCCUGGCCCCCGCCCUCUUGUACCAGUUCCUGAUGAAUGGCAUCCGACUGGGCACCUAUGGGCUGGCUGAGGCUGGGGGCUACCUGCACACAGCCGAAGGCACCCACAGUCCUGCCCGCAGCGCAGCAGCUGGGGCCAUGGCUGGGGUCAUGGGAGCCUACUUGGGGAGCCCCAUCUACAUGGUGAAGACACACCUGCAGGCACAGGCAGCCUCAGAAAUUGCUGUAGGGCACCAGUAUAAGCAUCAGGGCAUGUUUCAGGCGCUAACCGAGAUUGGCCAGAAACAUGGUCUGGUGGGGUUAUGGCGUGGGGCUCUGGGCGGCCUGCCCCGAGUUAUCGUCGGUUCCUCCACCCAGCUGUGCACCUUCUCAUCCACCAAGGACCUCCUGAGCCAGUGGGAGAUCUUUCCUCCCCAGAGCUGGAAGUUGGCGCUGGUGGCUGCCAUGAUGAGUGGCAUUGCAGUUGUCUUGGCCAUGGCACCCUUUGAUGUGGCCUGCACAAGGCUCUACAACCAGCCCACAGAUGCACAGGGCAAGGGCCUCAUGUACCGGGGGAUACUGGACGCUCUGCUGCAGACAGCUCGGACCGAGGGCAUUUUUGGCAUGUACAAGGAACCGAGUCCCCAAGUUCUCAGCAACAUCAUGCAGUGCUUCAGCGCCUUUACUGGGGACCAAAGAUGUUAGGAUCGUGAAGGGUCAGACUGGUCACCAGCUGUUCAAAGUCACCCAGGCUCCAGGGUGCAGGUGACAGAUUUUCGGGGCCAAGAGAUGACCUGUUGUCAGGGCUUGGGGUGGGGGAACAGAUGGAGACAGAACAUCAUCCAGGCCUGAGGUUUGGAAAUUGCCAAUUCCUGUUCCCCAGAGGACCUGGGUAUCAGUUACCCCAAACCUCUGGCCCACUCCUGCUUCCUUGGAGGAUCCCACCAGUGAGUCUCCCUGUUCUGUCCCUCCCAGCCCGAUUCUCCUGGGAACCCAGUCAUGAGAUACCCGCCCGUUCCUUCCUCCUUACGGGGGCUGAUUGAAGGUAAGCAAGAGAUCAGUCUGGUACUGGGGCAGCCUCAGCAAGGCCUGAUGAAGUGUCACGUCCUUUGCUACCUAAGGGGAUCAGAGUCAGGAUGCUUACCUGGAUCUCUGCGUCCCCGCUACCGCCCUUCCAGGACAUUACACACUCUCGGGCCCUCACCUGCUGGUUUUCCUUAGCUAUCUGCUGCUUGCCAGAGAGGACCCAGGCUUCUUGACAGCGGCCCCUCAGGGCCAGGUUCUCCAAACUGAGAGGCUGAACAGACUCCACAUGGACAGCCCUAGCCCCCUGCACGCCACCAACAUCCUCAAAGUGGUACCUGGAGUAGGGAAGCGGGGUCAGGAAGGGACAUCUCUGGUCGCCUCCCCGGGAGCAUCUUUAAGUUGCAGGCCUGGCUCCCGGCCCGUGCGUGGUCUCACCGCCCGGAUUAACCGUCGGCCGCGGGCCCCGCCCACUGGUCCGACCCCGCCCCUGCCAUUGGCCAGCCGGGGGCCAUUCCCUCACCGCGCAGCCGCUUCGCCCCGUACGUGGGCCUGCAGCUCGAGAAGUUCCACUAUCAGGCUCUGGUCCGUCACGGGAUGGCAGAAAACUUCUUGAUUGUCCGGGACCGGUCGGAGGUCGCUGGAGUGAGGCGAGGCAGACCCUGGUUGACCCCGGUCUCUUCCCACAACCCACCCAGUCAGCCGCCCCUGGGCGCCCCGGCCUUCUCACCUUACGUCAAUGGCCCCCAUGGGGAGGAUGGCGGAAAAGGCGCCCCCGAACAGCGGGCAGUCUCUCGUGGGCUCCAUGGGUCUGAGGCUGGGUUAUGGGCAUUAGAAAGGUUUAAAAGAAGUCCACAUUGGGUCACGUGGCAUCGGCUCCCUGGGUUUCGCAGCUGCCACCGCCACCCGGGUCUGGCUUAGCUCCCGGAUCCUUUAAGAUUUGGCUCCGCCCUGCGCUCUCGUUGGCCAAUCGGCGCCAAGACCCUGGGGGCGGGGGUCAGCGGCUUUGCUCCGGAAGCCGCGCUCUUAGGAGUGCGCCUGGCGGGACGGUGGGGUCUGCCUUGGGGUUGGACUUAGGGUUAGGGUCUAUGUCGCCCCCGGUGGUCACGAGCAUGCUCCCGCCAGCCUCCUCUUGAUUGAUUGAUUGAUUGAUUGAUUGACAGGUCUCGCUGUGUCGCCCAGGCUGUAAUGCAGUGGCGCGAUCACCGCUCACUGCAGUCUCCACCUCCAGGACUCAAGUGAUACUCCUGCCUCAGCCUCUUGAGUGGCUCCUGCUCCCGCCACCACGCCCGGCUAAAUUUUUAAUUACUUGUAGAAAUGGGGCGGGGUGGGGAGUGUCUCCCAAUCUUGCCCAGGCUGGCCUCAAACUCCUGGACUCAAGCGAUCCUCCCGCCUCGGCUCCCUAAGUGCUGGAAUUACAGGCGAGAGCCACAGCGCCUGGCCUCCUCGUCCUUUUCAAGUGGUCACACCUUCCAAGAAGGUCGCCUGAGACCCUCCUGAGGGGCAGGUGCUCGUCAAAGGGGCCCACGUCUAGGUAGGGUCUCUUGAGUCAGGAAAGCAUAGUUUCACGGUGUUCUGGGCCUCUGAAAGAAGAAUGGGCUGCCACCCAGACCGCUAAUUCAUAGAUCUGCUGCUGGGAAUUAGGGGAACAAUGCGUCCAGGUUAGGAUUCAGGUCUCACAUCUUCCUGAAAGUGAGAGCCAACCUGGGUAUUAGAAAUCUAAUUCCUCUCAAAUAUUUGCCUUGGGAAUGCUCCCGGGCAGGUGCAACCCCACCCCCAGCUCCACACACCUGGACAGAAGCACAGAUUAAACCCUCUUUUGUUUGUCUUUUA